AAUAAGGUUGAAAUGCAUUACCUUAUUUAUUCCUUAAAAUAACCCAAGAAGAUAAAGACUGUUGUUAUUCUCCUCUCUACAUCUGCCCAAACUGAGGCUUGUGGACGUGUGUAACUUGUCCAAGAGCUUCAUAGUAAUUGAUGAAGCAGAGUUUUAACCUGGCAAUUUGACCCUACAGAUGAACUCUUAUCUUGUGUGCUAUAGGUUUUUUUUUUUUCUAUCUAAGUCUCAUGACAUUGCUCAUCAGUAAGAUUUUUUUCAUUAAACUUUUUAUUUUGAGAUAAUUGUGGUUUCACAUAUAGUUAAGGGCAAAAAUCCAGAGAGAUUCUUUGUAUCCUUUACCCAGUUUUCCCCAGUGCUGCUGUCUUGCAAAACUAUAAUACUGUAUCGUAACCAAUAUGCUGAUAUUGAUACUGUCAAGAUAUAGAAUAUUUCUAUAACUACAAAAAUUCCUCUGAUUGCCUUUUUAUAGCCACAUCUACCUCUCCGACUGUCAUUUUAAGAGUGCAGCAUCUAACCAAAUGGAAUUAUUCAGCAUGUAAACUUUGGAGAUUGGUGUUUUUUCAUUCAGCAUAAUUCUCUGGAGAGUCAUCCAGGUUGUUGCAUGUAUUAGUAGGCCAUUUAUUUUACUGCCAAGUAGUAUUCCACAGUAUGGGUGUACCAUAGUUUAAUAUUCACCUGUUGAAAGACGUUUGGGUUGUUUCCAUUGUCAGGCUAUUAUGAAUAGAGCUGCUAUAAAUAUUUGUGUACAGGAUAAGUUUCAACUUUUCUUGGAUAAAUCACCAAAGUGCAGUUGCUGUGUUGUAUGUUAGUUGCAUGUGUCAUUUUAUAAAUGAAACUGCCAAACUGUUUUUCCAGAGCAGCCCAUGAAUUGAAAGCAAUUUUUAUGACUUAUUUUAUAUCCUUUGUAUUUAUAGAAUUUCAGUGGAAUUUCUACUUGAUACAAAUGACCCUAAAGCUCAAUAUCAAAUGCAAUUUUUAAUUUUUUUUGAGGCAUGGAUUUGUAAGGCCACUUUUUUUCUGGAAUGAGUCAUUUAACUGUUAGAUAAGCCUAAUGGUCUGCUCAGCUUACAUGGCAUAGUGAUAUCUUUUUUUUUUUCUCUACUCAUUAACUCUACUGUGUAUGAUAAAAGAAUAUGCUUCCUGGGAGUUUUUAAUAGUUAUUAAUAAAAUAAUUCCUUAUUUUUUAUAUAUAUAUUUAAAGGCACACCUAAUUAAUUUUGUCCUCAAAUAAAGCCCUCCAAAUGUUCAGGGAUUGAACUGCUGAGAGUGCUUUAUUAAGUCUAUAAUUAAAUACAGGUGAUAUUUAAUUGCAAUACUCACUAUGCAAGUGCCAUUACCCUGUAGUUCUCUGAUAAAAUUCAUUUAUAGAUGGUUCCUUCACAAGUAUUCCAUGCAAAUAGCUCUUAUGAUAAAUAUCUCUAAACCGUGGCUGGAACAUAGCCUCUCCACCAGAACAAUAUAAAGUAUAUUUAGUAGUAAUCUUAAGUCUUGUACAUAAUAUUGUAACCUCAUUGUUCAUUCUGUUGUAUGUUUUGUAUAAUAUAUUUUUCUGUGUGGUAUCUGGCUAUCGAUUAGUCCUGUAAUGGUAAUUAAUUAUAAAUAAGUUUCACUUCUUAUUUCCAAUUUUUUUCUUCAGAUUAAUUUAUCUAUGUUUUCAUGGUUUGGUUUUCAUGGUCCUUUCGAGGUCUGUGAUUUCAGAGUUUACAUAGUUCCAGAAUGAAUUUUUUACAGUUCCAAAAUAUUUAUUUGCAUAGGUGUAGCUCAGAAAUAGGUAGUAUUUUAAAAGUACUUUAUGCAUUUUAACUUCCAAAUAGGUAACAGGUGUUUAACAUCACAUAUAUAGGAAUUCAAAAGUUACAUUUUAAAAAUUAAAUGAAUAGGUUUGCAGGAAACUUGGAUUAUGAACAACUAGUAGUUACCUAUGACUUAACAAUUACAAAUUACAGAUGUAAUUUAUCAUGUAAUCACCAGAUACUUGUUCCUUCAUUGGCUGGAAUUUUCAAGUGAAAACUGUACUUCAAUAAACCUUAGGAAACUGUAAGCAUAAGGAUUGAGUCUUUUAAGUGAAUGCAAAUCUUAUUUUUUAAUUUUUUUUGCUAACAAUGAGCAUUAUGUGCAAAAGAGAACUUCAAUGAGUGUUGAAAGUUAUUAAUUAGUGGCAUGAUAUCAUGAAUAUGAAGUGAGCAACUUUAUGAAGAUUUGUCAACCUUGGCACUGUUGACAUUUUGGGUGGGAUUAUUUCUAAAUAUGGAUGGCUGUCUCAUGCAUUGUAGUAUGUUUAGCAGCAUCCUGGGUCUCUAAUCAUUAGAUGCUAGUAGCCCUCCUCCGCACAAGUGAUUCUAUUUAAAAAUGUCUCCAGAUGUUGUCAGAUGAGGGACAAAUCUUCCCUUUUGAGAACCACUGAACUUGAAUGAAAUGUGAUUGGGAAAAAGAUGACAUAUCCUAGAAUGAUUGAGAAAUUUAUGAAAGUUUUAGGAUGUAUCCCAAUACAUGUCAAUAGAUUAAUUUUAAUUAAGUAACAAAAGAAAUUUUAUUUCCCCAUGCGAUAGCUUUUAUACUAGCAGACAAGAUGGGUGUUCUUCCUUUUUCUCUUGGAGAAGAGAAUAUUUUUGCAAAACUUCACCAUUAUACUAUAGGGCAGGAAGACUGCCAUCACCAGAAUUCAGAUGCUGCCAUCCCCAAAGUUCAGAUGCUGCACUGUGGAGCCUAGGAUCCAGAUACUUCUCACCACUGCAUGAAUGGACAUUUGAAAGUGCCAUAGCCAAACACUUGCAAGCAUGGAGACCUCAUCAAUGCUUUCCUCAUUGAAUGAUGAGUGUAAAUCUGACAACUACAUUGAGCCUCACUACAAGGAAUGGUAUCGAGUAGCCAUUGAUAUUCUGAUUGAACACGGGUUAGAAGCAUACCAAGAAUUUCUUGUCCAGGAACGAGUUUCAGACUUUCUUGCUGAGGAAGAAAUUAAUUAUAUUUUGAAAAAUGUCCAGAAAGUUGCACAAAGCACAGCACAUGGUACUGAUGAUUCCUGUGAUGAUACCUUAUCUUCAGGGACCUACUGGCCUGUUGAGUCUGAUGUGGAAGCUCCAAAUCUUGACUUAGGCUGGCCAUAUGUGAUGCCCGGACUCUUAGGGGGCACCCAUAUAGAUCUCCUUUUUCAUCCACCAAGAGCACAUCUACUUACGAUAAAAGAAACUAUUCGGAAGAUGAUAAAAGAAGCAAGAAAGGUCAUUGCUUUAGUGAUGGAUAUAUUUACAGAUGUGGACAUUUUCAAAGAAAUCGUUGAGGCAUCAACUCGAGGAGUAUCUGUUUACAUUCUGCUUGAUGAGUCCAAUUUUAAUCAUUUUCUAAAUAUGACUGAGAAACAAGGUUGUUCAGUUCAGCGUCUCAGGAAUAUUCGAGUGCGAACAGUAAAAGGCCAAGAUUAUCUUUCAAAAACAGGGGCAAAAUUCCAUGGAAAAAUGGAACAGAAAUUUUUGUUAGUUGACUGCCAGAAAGUGAUGUACGGUUCUUACAGUUAUAUGUGGUCAUUUGAGAAAGCUCACCUCAGCAUGGUUCAGAUAAUUACAGGACAACUUGUUGAGUCCUUUGAUGAAGAAUUUAGAACUCUCUAUGCCAGAUCCUGUGUCCCUAGUUCAUUUGCUCAGGAAGAAUCAGCAAGGGUGAAGCAUGGAAAAGCCCUCUGGGAAAAUGGCACUUACCAGCAUUCGGUGUCUUCAUUAGCAUCUGUUUCCAGCCAGAGAAACCUUUUUGGUAGACAAGACAAGAUUCAUAAACUAGAUUCCAGUUACUUCAAAAACAGAGGGAUAUAUACUUUAAAUGAACAUGACAAAUAUAACAUAAGAAGUCACGGAUACAAACCUCAUUUUGUUCCUAACUUUAAUGGUCCAAACGCAAUACGUCAGUUUCAACCCAAUCAGAUAAAUGAAAAUUGGAAAAGGCAUAGUUAUGCUGGGGAACAGCCAGAAACAGUGCCAUACCUCCUGCUUAAUAGGGCUCUGAAUAGAACCAAUAAUCCACCUGGUAAUUGGAAAAAGCCAUCUGAUAGUCUCAGUGUGGCGUCCUCAUCACGGGAAGGCUAUGUAAGCCACCACAACACACCUGCCCAGAGUUUUGCCAAUCGGCUUGCGCAGAGAAAAACAACAAAUCUUGCAGACAGGAAUUCAAAUGUUCGGAGGUCUUUUAAUGGGACAGAUAACCAUAUCCGCUUUUUGCAACAACGAAUGCCAACCCUUGAACAUACCACAAAGUCAUUCCUACGUAACUGGAGAAUUGAAUCCUACUUAAAUGAUCAUUCAGAAGCUACACCGGACUCAAAUGGAUCAGCUUUAGGUGACCGAUUUGAGGGCUAUGAUAAUCCUGAGAAUUUGAAGGCCAAUGCCCUUUAUACUCAUUCUCGGCUUCGUUCCUCUUUAGUAUUUAAACCCACUUUACCUGAGCAAAAGGAAGUUAACAGUUGUACAACUGGCUCCUCAAAUUCAACUAUCAUUGGUUCUCAGGGAAGUGAGACACCUAAAGAGGUCCCAGACACCCCUACGAAUGUACAGCAUUUGACAGACAAACCCUUGCCAGAAUCAAUCCCCAAGCUCCCAUUGCAGUCAGAGGCACCAAAAAUGCACACCUUGCAGGUUCCUGAAAACCACUCAGUAGCCUUAAACCAAACUACAAAUGGCCAUACUGAAUCAAAUAACUAUAUAUAUAAAACCUUGGGUGUAAAUAAGCAGACAGAAAAUCUAAAGAAUCAACAGACUGAGAAUCUACUUAAAAGGCGAAGUUUCCCGUUAUUUGACAACUCAAAAGCCAACUUAGAUCCUGGAAAUAGUAAGCAUUAUGUAUAUAGUACACUUACCAGGAAUCGAGUUAGACAACCAGAAAAGCCCAAAGAAGAUUUGCUGAAAAGUUCUAAAAGCAUGCACAAUGUGACUCAUAACUUGGAGGAGGAUGAGGAGGAAGUUACCAAGAGAAACUCUCCAAGUGGCACUACUACCAAAUCAGUUUCCAUUGCUGCUUUACUUGAUGUGAAUAAAGAGGAAUCUAACAAAGAACUUGCUUCAAAGAAGGAAGUUAAGGGUUCCCCAAGUUUUUUGAAAAAGGGGUCUCAGAAGUUAAGGUCAUUACUUAGCCUUACCCCAGAUAAGAAAGAAAAUCUAUCCAAAAAUAAAGCACCUGCCUUUUAUAGAUUGUGUAGUAGCUCUGACACAUUAGUUUCUGAGGGUGAAGAAAAUCAAAAACCAAAGAAAUCAGACACAAAAGUUGAUUCAUCUCCUAGAAGAAAGCAUUCUUCCUCAUCGAAUUCUCAAGGCAGCAUCCACAAGAGUAAGGAAGAUGUAACAGUUAGCCCAUCUCAAGAGAUAAAUGCUCCACCAGAUGAAAAUAAAAGAACACCUUCUCCAGGUCCAGUUGAAAGCAAGUUCUUGGAAAGGGCAGGAGAUGCCUCUGCCCCAAGAUUUAACACUGAACAGAUCCAAUACCGAGAUUCAAGGGAGAUUAAUGCAGUUGUUACCCCUGAAAGAAGACCUACUUCUUCUCCAAGGCCAACGUCCAGUGAGCUUCUACGAUCUCAUUCAACUGAUCGGCGUGUUUACAGUCGUUUUGAGCCGUUUUGUAAGAUUGAGAGCUCUAUUCAGCCAACAAGCAACAUGCCAAAUACCAGUAUAAAUCGCCCAGAAAUAAAAUCUGCGACUAUGGGCAACAGUUAUGGCAGGUCUAGUCCAUUGCUUAAUUACAACACUGGUGUUUAUCGCUCAUAUCAACCCAAUGAGAACAAGUUUCGAGGAUUUAUGCAAAAGUUUGGAAACUUUAUACACAAAAAUAAAUAGCUAUUAAAAUGCAAAAUGAAUGAGGCUAUCAAUAUUUGUCCAAAGAAAAUUGUGGACAGUCUUUGUAACAUGCCAAUAGAUUUUCCUAAGGACAGAAUUAUGGGUAUGAUGUAUAUGUUCACCAGUGUCCUAGUAUAAAGUUAUUUUUCUGUGUGAUAAAGUUAGGGUCUGCUGUAGAUAGAAUUUCUCUGUAAACACAUUAUUUGUAAGUGGUAAUGGUAAAAAUAAUAGAUGUAUUUAAAUCAUUUUCUUUAGACUGAAGAUUUUAAGUCUCACUUAGAAAUUUUUGUGGACGAUGUAUGGUGUAUGGUGUAUGGUGUAUGGAUUUUAACCAUUUCCUUUUAAAAAGGUCAUACUACCCUCAGUAACCCUUUAUAACAUGUGUUUAUAGUGUUUUCAUAUCUUCAAAAAUAUAAGCAAAUGGGACAAAGCCCUUUUUUAAGAUUAACUUGAAGUUCUACGGGAUAACUUGUUAUAUUUUAUUAAUAUUAUUUUUUCUGUGGAUCAUUGUACAGCUGUUUGGGCAACAGCAGUACCUUUUACAUUUUUUAUUUUUUAUUUUUUUUUCUGCCUGAAGUGUUUGCAAAGUAUCAGCCUCAUGUAGUAUAAUGACAUUCGUAGGAAUUUAUUUUCCUCAGCCUUUGAAAACGGUCUGGGAUGUGCUUCUUUCUACACUGGACCCAGGGAGCUGUCCCCCUCUUACCCAUAGGCUGCUGAUUUUUUAUAGUCAUUCCUUACUUCACAUUUAGGACAAACCAGUAGGAAUUUAGAAAAUCUGAAUGAUUCCCCCUCCUUUUUCUAUUGUAUAAAAGCUUUUAGAAAUGUAAAUUUCUGCCUAAAUUUUUGUUAGAUUGGCAUGACAAUGCUAAGGGGUCUUGCUUGCGAAAAUUCUUGCUCUUUUUUUUUUUCUUUUGAGAUGGAGUCUCGCUCUGUCACCCAGGCUAGAGUGCAGUGGCGCAAUCUUGGCUCACUGCAACCUCUGCCUCCCAAGUUCAAACGAUUCUCCUGCCUCAGCCUCCUGAGUAGCUGGGAUUACAGGUGCGCACCACCACACCCGGCUAAUUUUUGUAUUUUCAGAAGAGAUGGGAUUUCACCAUGUUGGCCAGUCUAGUCUCAAACUCCUGACCUCGUGAUCCUCCCGCCUCGGCCUCCCAGAGUGCUGGGAUUACAGGUCUUGCUCUUCUUUAAGUUGUGCCAAAUAUGAUAUGACUGCAUAGUGUUUUUGUAAGAAUACCAUUGGGAAAAUGAGAAGUUUUACUGGGCUAGUUCUUCCAUGAUUUGAGGAUGAUAUUCAGAUUAUAAGAUACCCUUUGUCUUUCUUACAGUAAUGAAGUAUAAGCUCCAUAUCUGUUCCAGAGACUUUAACUUGACUUUGCUUCAUUCACAAAGAACAGAGUUCAAGAAGCAGUGCAUCCUGUGAGAAGUGUGAAGUGUUUGUACAUCACUUUAAAUAUAUUACUUAAUAUAUUCUAAGUUGCUGUGUGGAGCAGUAUACUGUUGUUUUAAAAAUGCAAGAUUCAGACAAAUUUUAAUAUUGUCUCAUUAAAAUAAUUUAAAUAAUGGUAUAAAAUAUCUAUAUCAUUAAAAUAAUUUUCCAUAGUGUUUAGAAACCAUGAAAAAGAAAACAUAGCAGGAGAAAAUAUGACAGGAAAAGAAAACCUAACAAAGCCCAGAACCCACAGUUAACCAAACUAGACUGACUUUGUUAUUACCCAUUCUUUGUUAGUAUUGGAUAGGGAAUUAGGAUAAUGAGCCAUUAGGCAGUUCUGAAAUGGAAAGCCCUGAAAUUUAGUGCAAUGUAACUUUAAAACUGAAAUUAUAUAAAGAGUAGAAGUUUAAUCAUGUUUAAUUACAACCAAAAGCCUGUUGCCUUUUUGUACAGAAAUCUCCUUAAUUUCAGGACAUGUAGAUAGCUUAUAGAAACAUCCUUUUAAAUAGUUUGUGAGCUCUUCCUCUUCAGUGGAAUUGAGGAAUACAGAAUGCUUUAUUUCAUCAUCCCCUGACAGGUGACUUAGGCUUUGCACAGCAGAUUUAUUUUUCUCUGCGUUUUUUAAAAAUUGUUUUUCUUGUAUCUUUUUUCUUCAAAAAUAUCUAUAUUUGAGAAUAUGUACAUAACAACUUUCCAAAGUCUCUGUGGCCAAAACCUCUCCAGGGAUAAGACUGAGCAAGAAUAUAAUACUUCAAAAAAUGUACAGCUACUGUUUAAGUUUUAAACAGACACCAUCACAGUUUGUGGAUGAAAUAGUUUUAAGCCAUAUACUUUCUGUCUUUUUUUCCCCAUAUUAAUAUUGGGGGGCGGAUAAUAUCACUUUGAUGUACAUUGAUAUUAAAGUUUGGUAAUGCAGCUUUUACUGUCUACAUGGUACUGUACAUUAGUUUUUAAGCAGAAACACAAGAAAAAUGGGUAUAAUUUCAAAGUAGUUCUUGGCAGAUGGCUAGAGAAUACUGCAAGUGACCCUGUAUCCCGAAUACACAGAUAUCCCUCUAUUACAAGUUUGGGAUUAGCCAUAAUUCUGACAUGGUGUGUUCAGGUAUGGGUAUAUGUUGUCAGUCUACACUUGUGGAAGCAAAUAUCUUGUUUAAUCAAGAUGAUGUCUAGUGUCACCUAAAUAAUGCAAAAAGUUUAAUUCUGGAUGAAUUCAGCUUUACUCAAGAUCCACAUAUUCAAGUAUCAUUCCACAGAUAUUCACAGAACACAGAAAUAUCUGUGUUCUGCCUUAUGCCUGUGGCUAAGGGAUGCAAAGUAGAAUUGCUUUACAUUGACUAUAUAUGUGACAUGUACGUUGCUGUUUUUUUUAAAAUAACUUUAUCAUGAUAUUCAGGUAGAUCCUGGGUUCUAGAAUAUUUAAAACAAAAGGAUAAAAUGAUAAACCAAAGAGUCAACUUGUUAACUUUUCUUUUUUAAGAGAUGGGUUUUCACUAGUAUGCCCAGUCUGGACUCCAAGUCCUGGGCUCAAACGAUCCUCCAGCCUCAGGUUCCUGAGUAGCUCAACAUUUUAUGUAUGUACGAUAUUAUAAAGAAAUAUUCUUCCAAAUGAACUUUUGUUUUUAGAUCAAUAAAUGAAUAAUAAAUAAUUUUGUACAAACAUCAA